GGAGCCUAGCGGAGGACGUCGGGGAUUGAACUGACUUUGGGGGACAGUGGACAGGCGGAGGCGCUCACACUUCUCCUCAGCCCUCGGCUUUUCUGUGGAAUCCCAGUCAGGAAGCGGCCGAAUGCGGGAGGCGGGGGAGGGAACAAAAAGGUGACGAGGAAGGGGCCUGCCGACCUCCGGGGCAGCGCUGGCCAGGAGCUUGGGGCCUGCGAGUCUUCCCAGCUGUAGACAGAGCGCCUCUGAGCCCCGAGGCCGGGCCGCCCCACAGCAGAGGAGCACGAGGUUUCAUUUGGCCUUGGCCAGUAGCUCAAAGGGGGCUUCGUUAUUUUCAGGCCAUGAGCGACCCCAGCACCAAAAUCAGGGACACACAUCGAAGGCUUCUCUUGGACUCUGUUUUAGAGUCCCCUGGCAGGCUGUUAACGUUCCCAAGAGAUAAUACAAACGUUUCGUCAGUUUCAGCCACAAAAAUAAUCAAAUAAUCGUCAAUUGAUGAAUGCUGAGGCCGCCUCGACAGCAGCCAGCGUCCUCCCCAGAUGGUUUGCGUGGGGUGGGGGGAAUCACGAUGCCCCAGUUCUUUCUUCUCCCCACGUGAGAAGCAAGGAAAGUCGGGUGAGAGGCCUUAUUAUGUUUUCCCUGAAGUGCAUUCUGCUUGACGAUGCUGUUGUCAAUGUACAGCUCGCCCUGAGGUGUCUUGUCAGUGUUUUGUUAAUGGAAUUGCUGGCCAUAUUUUAUCUAGGACUAAGCUCUCAUUCAACAGUUGGCUGUGUUUUAUAACACUACUUACGGACCACGGAGGCUCGGCAGGCAGUCAACUUGUAUUUUGCAGACAUACCUUAGUUUUCUCAUGUAGGUACUGCACAAACUGGCUUCGUAUCUUGCACUAUGAGUGUAGGCUGACUCUUCCAGCAUAGUCUCCUUCGGGGUGGCGCUGAAUAUCCCCUCAUUUCAGCUUUUCAUGGUGCUCCUUUGCCUCAUUUUUUUAAACCAUAAUGUCUAGCCUGGUCUCAGCUCCAAGGCAAGAACAGAAAUACAGGUAAGGACAGAAAUAUUGUGGCAAAUUCUACCACCAUUUGGAUGAAUAAUAAUAAAACGUUCAUUUAUUUUAUAGCAUCUGCAAACAUCCCAAAACCUUUCAACCAAAAUAUGUAUAGAUGAGUGUGCAGACCAAAGUAAGGACAUCAGUAUGUUACAUUUAAAAAUAAGUCAAGGUUAAAGGCGGUGUCCUCUUUUAAGAACAUCGCAAAUACAAUUCCAGUACUCCAAGUACGUAUUCUGUACCCAGCCACCUGGGAGGACUGAGAGACCUAAUGGUUUUCUGCUUUCUGGAACUUCUAUGCCAAUUGUGACUUUCUCACCCAAAUUUGUAAAUUCGCAAAUUAACAUGCAGCGAAUAAUUACAAUUGUAAACACCUGGAAGUGGAAAAGGCCGUGAGGAUAAAUUGAGAGGAAGAGUAAACCUAAUACCAUAAGUUGCAUACCAGCAGAUCUGAGUAUCGUCAUGAAUAAUUGGUUAGCUUUUCCACAUGCCUUAGAAGUUUCAGCAAGCACCUAGCGAACAUCUUAAUCCAAAUUUCUCAAAAAAUGAGAGAUUUUAUUUAAGAUCAUUCCUCAAUUUAUCUUAGACUUUCAGCUACAUAGUUAGUCCGGUAGUGUAACAGUAACGGGUUUUACGUAAAUGCCAGGGGAAAAGAGAGGAAAGCUAAAUAACCAAGUAAAUCUGUAUCUAAUUAACAAAUUGGCUAAAUAAGGUGUUAUCAGCUGCUUGAUAUAGAGCUGAUAAAAUCUUCAGCUAGGCAUACUUGAGGCCUGAUUACAGAAGUGACCGUAGUCCACCCACACACCUGAAAUUUAUUUAAGAGACCAAGCUAGGCUCUUCCUGGCCUUUAGGAAGAGGACUGGCAUGGAGAAAUAUGUUCCUCACUAGUUCUCCCAAGCCAUGGCACGUCCCAACAAAUUCCUCCUUUGGUUUUGCUGCUUUGCCUGGCUGUGUUUUCCUAUUAGCCUUGGUUCUCAGGCUUCUGGGGGAGAAGCUCAGAUUGCUGCUAGUGCUGAGUUGGAAUCUGGGGCUAUGCCUUGGUCCUUGCUGCAGCAUAUAGAUGAGAGAGACAGAGCUGGCCUCCUUCCCGCGCUUUUCAAAGUUCUAUCUGUUGGGCGAGGUGGGUCACCUAGGCUGCAGCCAGACUCCAGAGCUUUGCACUACAUGAAGAAGCUCUAUAAGACAUAUGCUACCAAGGAAGGGAUUCCUAAAUCCAAUAGAAGUCACCUCUACAACACUGUUCGGCUCUUCACCCCCUGUACCCGGCACAAGCAGGCUCCUGGAGACCAGGUAACAGGAAUCCUUCCAUCAGUGGAACUGCUAUUUAACCUGGAUCGCAUUACUACCGUUGAACACUUACUCAAGUCAGUCUUGCUGUACAAUAUCAACAACUCAGUUUCUUUUUCCUCUGCUGUCAAAUGUGUGUGCAAUCUAAUGAUAAAGGAGCCAAAGUCUUCUAGCAGGACUCUCGGCAGAGCUCCAUACUCAUUUACCUUUAACUCACAGUUUGAAUUUGGAAAGAAACACAAAUGGAUUCAGAUUGAUGUGACCAGCCUCCUUCAACCUUUAGUGGCCUCCAACAAGAGAAGUAUUCACAUGUCUAUAAAUUUUACUUGCAUGAAAGACCAGCUGGAGCAUCCUUCAGCACAGAAUGGUUUGUUUAACAUGACUCUGGUGUCCCCCUCACUGAUCUUAUAUUUGAAUGACACAAGUGCUCAGGCUUAUCACAGCUGGUAUUCCCUUCACUAUAAAAGGAGGCCUUCCCAGGGUCCUGACCAGGAGAGAAGUCUGUCUGCCUAUCCUGUGGGAGAAGAGGCUGCUGAGGAUGGGAGAUCUUCCCAUCACCGUCACCGCAGAGGUCAGGAAACUGUCAGUUCUGAAUUGAAGAAGCCCUUGGGCCCAGCUUCCUUCAAUCUGAGUGAAUACUUCAGACAAUUUCUUCUUCCCCAAAAUGAGUGUGAGCUCCAUGACUUUAGACUUAGCUUUAGUCAGCUGAAGUGGGACAACUGGAUUGUGGCUCCGCACAGGUACAACCCUCGAUACUGUAAAGGGGACUGUCCAAGGGCAGUUGGACAUCGGUAUGGCUCUCCAGUUCACACCAUGGUACAGAACAUCAUCUAUGAGAAGCUGGACUCCUCAGUGCCAAGACCGUCAUGUGUACCUGCCAAAUACAGCCCCUUGAGUGUUUUGACCAUUGAGCCCGAUGGCUCAAUUGCCUAUAAAGAGUACGAAGAUAUGAUAGCUACAAAGUGCACCUGUCGUUAACAAAUGGUCCUCUUAAAACCUUGAGCCUAUUUGGCAAAGUAACUACUGUGUGCCUAUGUGUGCCUUCAAGAGAAAGCUUCAUAUAUUAAGUCUCUAAAUGUAGCAUAUGUUAUAUAAAGAGGAGCCUGUGUAGGUUAGUACCUUCUAUGGCAUCUAUCAGGAUAAAGGGAUAACAUCAAUUGUUGCUACAGAGCCUUUUUUUAUUUCCAAAUUUAAAUGAAAUAUAAUUAUUGUGGAGAACUUUACAUUUUUUUCCUUGAGUGAUUUUUUUUCUUUUCAUAGGAGUCUUAUUCUUGAUAGGGAAAAAACCUUAAUUAGCAUCAAUCCUGGAUGGACUUGCAGCUAUAAAUAGGCAAUUCAGAUUGCUGUAGUCUUAAUAGAAGAAUAAAUUUCUGUCAAUGGCA